UACAGGGGUUGCAACUGGGAGCCUAGGGGGCCCCAAGGCAUCUCCAGGCCCAAUCUACCUCUGGGCUUUUCUCAAGCUCUCCCUAGGAUUACUGCGGUUUCCUCCUGGCGCCUCUCGUCUUGGACAGCCAUGCCCCCCUCCAUGCUGCACUAAUGGCUCAGCCUGGGGCCCUAGGGACCUCUCCUACCCCCCAGACUGCUCUGUCGGCCCCCUUUCCCCCCUACUGCUGAAACCCAAUCCUCUGCAGCAGCGCCGGCUCAGCACCGCCGGCUCAGCACCGCUCCGCAGCCCCUGCCUGCCACGGUCAGCUACGUCCCACCUGGUCUGCUGCGGAGUCCCCAGCCCAGUGCCUAGCCCAGUGGAGCCACCGCCUGUUCCUCGGGAAGGAACAGUGGGACCUGACCGGCCAGAUCACCUCCUCCAAUCCUGCCAGGCUAGUGCCUCCCUGCCUUCCAACCUUGGCUGUCUCCCACCCUCUCUUCUCCUCUCCUUGCCUGGCCUCCUGAAUCCUAUCUUAGCCUCCUUAGCCCCCUGACUGACUCUCUCUCGCUUCUUCCAAGCCUCUGUAGCUGGUUCCGCUCCUGGGUUCUGGCCAUGAAGCCCACCUCAGGCCCAGAGGAGGCCCGGCGGCCAGCCUCGGACAUCCGCGUGUUCGCCAGCAACUGCUCGAUGCACGGGCUGGGCCACGUCUUCGGGCCAGGCAGCCUGAGCCUGCGCCGGGGGAUGUGGGCAGCGGCCGUGGUCCUGUCAGUGGCCACCUUCCUCUACCAGGUGGCUGAGAGGGUGCGCUACUACAGGGAGUUCCACCACCAGACUGCCCUGGAUGAGCGAGAAAGCCACCGGCUCAUCUUCCCGGCUGUCACCCUGUGCAACAUCAACCCACUGCGCCGCUCGCGCCUAACGCCCAACGACCUGCACUGGGCUGGGUCUGCGCUGCUGGGCCUGGAUCCCGCAGAGCACGCCGCCUUCCUGCGCGCCCUGGGCCGGCCCCCUGCACCGCCCGGCUUCAUGCCCAGUCCCACCUUUGACAUGGCGCAACUCUAUGCCCGUGCUGGGCACUCCCUGGAUGACAUGCUGCUGGACUGUCGCUUCCGUGGCCAACCUUGUGGGCCUGAGAACUUCACCACGAUCUUCACCCGGAUGGGAAAGUGCUACACAUUUAACUCUGGCGCUGAUGGGGCAGAGCUGCUCACCACUACUAGGGGUGGCAUGGGCAAUGGGCUGGACAUCAUGCUGGACGUGCAGCAGGAGGAAUAUCUACCUGUGUGGAGGGACAAUGAGGAGACCCCGUUUGAGGUGGGGAUCCGAGUGCAGAUCCACAGCCAGGAGGAGCCGCCCAUCAUCGAUCAGCUGGGCUUGGGGGUGUCCCCGGGCUACCAGACCUUUGUUUCUUGCCAGCAGCAGCAGCUGAGCUUCCUGCCACCGCCCUGGGGCGAUUGCAGUUCAGCAUCUCUGAACCCCAACUAUGAGCCAGAGCCCUCUGAUCCCCUAGGCUCCCCCAGCCCCAGCCCCAGCCCUCCCUAUACCCUUAUGGGGUGUCGCCUGGCCUGCGAAACCCGCUACGUGGCUCGGAAGUGCGGCUGCCGAAUGGUGUACAUGCCAGGCGACGUGCCAGUGUGCAGCCCCCAGCAGUACAAGAACUGUGCCCACCCGGCCAUAGAUGCCAUGCUUCGCAAGGACUCGUGCGCCUGCCCCAACCCGUGCGCCAGCACGCGCUACGCCAAGGAGCUCUCCAUGGUGCGGAUCCCGAGCCGCGCCGCCGCGCGCUUCCUGGCCCGGAAGCUCAACCGCAGCGAGGCCUACAUCGCGGAGAACGUGCUGGCCCUGGACAUCUUCUUUGAGGCCCUCAACUAUGAGACCGUGGAGCAGAAGAAGGCCUAUGAGAUGUCAGAGCUGCUUGGUGACAUUGGGGGCCAGAUGGGGCUGUUCAUCGGGGCCAGCCUGCUCACCAUCCUCGAGAUCCUAGACUACCUCUGUGAGGUGUUCCGAGACAAGGUCCUGGGAUAUUUCUGGAACCGACAGCACUCCCAAAGGCACUCCAGCACCAAUCUGCUUCAGGAAGGGCUGGGCAGCCAUCGAACCCAAGUUCCCCACCUCAGCCUGGGCCCCAGCACUCUGCUCUGUUCCGAAGACCUCCCACCCCUCCCUGUGCCGUCACCAAGACUCUCUCCGCCUCCCACCGCACCUGCUACCUUGUCACACAGCUCUAGACCUGCUGUCUGUGUCCUCGGAGCCCCGCCCUGACAUCCUGGACAUGCCUAGCCUGCACGUAGCUUUUCCGUCUUCACCCCAAAUAAAGUCCUAAUGCAUCAGC